GUGGCCGCUGAGUUGCCGGCGCCGGCUGAGCCAGCGGACGCCGCGUUCCUUGGCGGCCGCCGGUUCCCGGGAAGUUACGUGGCGAAGCCGGCUUCCGAGGAGACGCCGGGAGGCCACGGGUGCUGCUGACGGGCGGGCGACCGGGCGAGGCCGACGUGGCCGGGCUGCGAAAGCUGCGGGAGGCCGAGUGGGUGGCCGCGCUCGGAGGGAGGUGCCGGUCGGGCGCGCCCCGUGGAGAAGACCCGGGCGGGGCGGGCGCUUCCCGGACUUUUGUCCGAGUUGAAUUCCCUCCCCCUGGGCCGGGCCUUUCCGGCCGCCCCCGCCCGUGCCCCGCUCGCUCUCGGGAGAUGUUUAUUUGGGCUGUGGCGUGAGGAGCGGGCGGGCCAGCGCCGCGGAGUUUCGGGUCCGAGGAGCCUCGCGCGGCGCUGGAGAGAGACAAGAUGUCCGCCAGAGCUGCGGCCGCCAAGGAGGAAAGGCUUUGUUUCCGUAUUACACAGAAUGUCACUUUGUUCCUGAAGUGUGAUCUCUGGUACUUAAUAUGCAAGACAACACACUUUUUAAGAGGUUAUUUCAAGUAUGGAGAGAAAUACGUUUUCAAUGGAUUGCCACAGUAAGAGCACAGCAAUGGAGGAAACAGCUAUAUGGGAACAACAUACAGUGACGCUUCACAGGGCUCCUGGAUUUGGAUUUGGAAUUGCAAUAUCUGGUGGACGAGAUAAUCCUCAUUUUCAGAGUGGGGAAACGUCAAUAGUGAUUUCAGAUGUGCUGAAAGGAGGACCAGCUGAAGGACAGCUACAGGAAAAUGACCGAGUUGCAAUGGUUAACGGAGUUUCAAUGGAUAAUGUUGAACAUGCUUUUGCUGUUCAGCAACUAAGGAAAAGUGGGAAAAAUGCAAAAAUUACAAUUAGAAGGAAGAAGAAAGUUCAAAUACCAGUAAGUCGUCCUGAUCCUGAACCAGUAUCUGAUAAUGAAGAAGAUAGUUAUGAUGAGGAAAUACAUGAUCCAAGAAGUGGCCGGAGUGGUGUGGUUAACAGAAGGAGUGAGAAGAUUUGGCCGAGGGAUAGAAGUGCAAGUAGAGAGAGGAGCUUGUCCCCGCGGUCAGACAGGCGGUCAGUGGCUUCCAGCCAGCCUGCUAAACCUACUAAAGUCACACUGGUGAAAUCCCGGAAAAAUGAAGAAUAUGGUCUUCGAUUGGCAAGCCAUAUAUUUGUUAAGGAAAUUUCACAAGAUAGUUUGGCAGCAAGAGAUGGCAAUAUUCAAGAAGGUGAUGUUGUAUUGAAGAUAAAUGGUACUGUGACAGAAAAUAUGUCAUUGACAGAUGCAAAGACAUUGAUAGAAAGGUCUAAAGGCAAAUUAAAAAUGGUAGUUCAAAGAGAUGAACGGGCUACGCUAUUGAAUGUCCCUGAUCUUUCUGACAGCAUCCACUCUGCUAAUGCCUCUGAGAGAGACGACAUUUCAGAAAUUCAGUCACUGGCAUCAGAUCAUUCUGGUCGAUCACACGAUAGGCCUCCCCGCCGCAGCCGGUCACGAUCUCCUGACCAGCGGUCAGAGCCUUCUGAUCAUUCCAGGCACUCGCCGCAGCAGCCAAGCAAUGGCAGUCUCCGGAGUAGAGAUGAAGAGAGAAUUUCUAAACCUGGGGCUGUCUCAACUCCUGUAAAGCAUGCUGAUGAUCACACACCUAAAACAGUGGAAGAAGUUACAGUUGAAAGAAAUGAGAAACAAACACCUUCUCUUCCAGAACCAAAGCCUGUGUAUGCCCAAGUUGGGCAACCAGAUGUGGAUUUACCUGUCAGUCCAUCUGAUGGUGUCCUACCUAAUUCAACUCAUGAAGAUGGGAUUCUUCGGCCCAGCAUGAAAUUGGUAAAAUUCAGAAAAGGAGAUAGUGUGGGUUUGCGGCUGGCUGGUGGAAAUGAUGUUGGAAUAUUUGUAGCUGGCGUUCUAGAAGAUAGCCCUGCAGCCAAGGAAGGCUUAGAGGAAGGUGAUCAAAUUCUCAGGGUAAACAACGUAGAUUUUACAAAUAUCAUAAGAGAAGAAGCCGUCCUUUUCCUGCUUGACCUCCCUAAAGGAGAAGAAGUGACCAUAUUGGCUCAGAAGAAGAAGGAUGUUUAUCGUCGCAUUGUAGAAUCAGAUGUAGGAGAUUCUUUCUAUAUUAGAACCCAUUUUGAAUAUGAAAAGGAAUCUCCCUAUGGACUUAGUUUUAACAAAGGAGAGGUGUUCCGUGUUGUGGAUACCUUGUACAAUGGAAAACUGGGCUCUUGGCUUGCUAUUCGAAUUGGUAAAAAUCAUAAGGAGGUAGAACGAGGCAUCAUCCCUAAUAAGAACAGAGCUGAGCAGCUAGCCAGUGUACAGUAUACACUUCCAAAAACAGCAGGCGGAGACCGUGCUGACUUCUGGAGAUUCAGAGGUCUUCGCAGCUCCAAGAGAAAUCUUCGAAAAAGCAGAGAGGAUUUGUCCGCUCAGCCUGUUCAAACAAAGUUUCCAGCUUAUGAAAGAGUGGUUCUUCGAGAAGCUGGAUUUCUGAGGCCUGUAACCAUUUUUGGACCAAUAGCUGAUGUUGCCAGAGAAAAGCUGGCAAGAGAAGAACCAGAUAUUUAUCAAAUUGCAAAGAGUGAACCACGAGACGCUGGAACUGACCAACGUAGCUCUGGCAUUAUUCGCCUGCAUACAAUAAAGCAAAUCAUAGAUCAAGACAAACAUGCUUUAUUAGAUGUAACACCAAAUGCAGUUGAUCGUCUUAACUAUGCCCAGUGGUAUCCAAUUGUUGUAUUUCUUAACCCUGAUUCUAAGCAAGGAGUAAAAACAAUGAGAAUGAGGUUAUGUCCAGAAUCUCGGAAAAGUGCCAGGAAGUUAUACGAGCGAUCUCAUAAACUUCGUAAAAAUAAUCACCAUCUUUUUACAACUACAAUUAACUUAAAUUCAAUGAAUGAUGGUUGGUAUGGUGCGCUGAAAGAAGCAAUUCAACAACAGCAAAACCAGCUGGUAUGGGUUUCCGAGGGAAAGGCGGAUGGUGCUACAAGUGAUGACCUUGAUUUGCAUGAUGAUCGUCUGUCCUACCUGUCAGCUCCAGGUAGUGAAUACUCAAUGUAUAGCACGGACAGUAGACACACUUCUGACUAUGAAGACACAGACACAGAAGGCGGGGCCUACACUGAUCAAGAACUAGAUGAAACUCUUAAUGAUGAGGUUGGGACUCCACCGGAGUCUGCCAUUACACGGUCCUCUGAGCCUGUAAGAGAGGACUCCUCUGGAAUGCAUCAUGAAAACCAAACAUAUCCUCCUUACUCACCACAAGCGCAGCCACAACCAAUUCAUAGAAUAGACUCCCCUGGAUUUAAGCCAGCCUCUCAACAGAAAGCAGAAGCUUCAUCUCCAGUCCCUUACCUUUCGCCUGAAACAAACCCAGCAUCAUCAACCUCUGCUGUUAAUCAUAAUGUAAAUUUAACUAAUGUCAGACUGGAGGAGCCCACCCCAGCUCCUUCCACCUCUUACUCACCACAAGCUGAUUCUUUAAGAACACCAAGUACUGAGGCAGCUCACAUAAUGCUAAGAGAUCAAGAACCAUCAUUGUCGUCGCAUGUAGAUCCAACAAAGGUGUAUAGAAAGGAUCCAUAUCCCGAGGAAAUGAUGAGGCAGAACCAUGUUUUGAAACAGCCAGCCGUUAGUCACCCAGGGCACAGGCCAGACAAAGAGCCUAAUCUGACCUAUGAACCCCAACUCCCAUACGUAGAGAAACAAGCCAGCAGAGACCUCGAGCAGCCCACAUACAGAUACGAGUCCUCAAGCUAUACGGACCAGUUUUCUCGAAACUAUGAACAUCGUCUGCGAUACGAAGAUCGCGUCCCCAUGUAUGAAGAACAGUGGUCAUAUUAUGAUGACAAACAGCCCUACCCAUCUCGGCCACCUUUUGAUAAUCAGCACUCUCAAGACCUUGACUCCAGACAGCAUCCCGAAGAGUCCUCAGAACGAGGGUACUUUCCACGUUUUGAAGAGCCAGCCCCUCUGUCUUACGACAGCAGACCACGUUACGAACAGGCACCUAGAGCAUCCGCCCUGCGGCACGAAGAGCAGCCAGCUCCUGGGUAUGACACACAUGGUAGACUCAGACCGGAAGCCCAGCCCCACCCUUCAGCAGGGCCCAAGCCUGCAGAGUCCAAGCAGUAUUUUGAGCAAUAUUCACGCAGUUACGAGCAAGUACCACCCCAAGGAUUUACCUCUAGAGCAGGUCAUUUUGAGCCUCUCCAUGGUGCUGCAGCUGUCCCUCCGCUGAUACCUUCAUCUCAGCAUAAGCCAGAAGCUCUGCCUUCAAACACCAAACCACUGCCUCCACCCCCAACUCAAACCGAAGAAGAGGAAGAUCCAGCAAUGAAGCCACAGUCUGUACUCACCAGAGUUAAGAUGUUUGAAAACAAAAGAUCUGCAUCCUUAGAGACCAAGAAGGAUGUAAAUGACACUGGCAGUUUUAAGCCUCCAGAAGUAGCAUCUAAACCUUCAGGUGCUCCCAUCAUUGGUCCCAAACCCACUUCUCAGAAUCAAUUCAGUGAACAUGACAAAACUCUGUACAGGAUCCCAGAACCUCAAAAACCUCAACUGAAGCCACCUGAAGAUAUUGUUCGGUCCAAUCAUUAUGACCCUGAAGAAGAUGAAGAAUAUUAUCGAAAACAGCUGUCAUACUUUGACCGAAGAAGUUUUGAGAAUAAGCCUCCUGCACACAUUGCUGCCAGCCAUCUCUCCGAGCCUGCAAAGCCAGCUCAUUCUCAGAAUCAAUCAAAUUUUUCUAGUUAUUCUUCAAAAUUUCUUGGCUCUUACACUAGCUAUGACUACUUGAAAAGGAACGUCAAGUGGGGAAAGCCUCCUGAAGCUGAUGGUGUGGAUAGAUCAUUUGGCGAGAAACGCUAUGAACCCAUCCAGGCCACUCCCCCUCCUCCUCCAUUGCCCUCGCAGUAUGCCCAGCCAUCUCAGCCUGUCACCAGCGCGUCUCUCCACAUACAUUCUAAGGGAGCACAUGGUGAAGGUAAUUCAGUGUCAUUGGAUUUUCAGAAUUCCUUAGUGUCCAAACCAGACCCACCUCCAUCUCAGAAUAAGCCAGCAACUUUCAGACCACCAAACCGAGAAGAUACUGCUCAGGCAGCUUUCUAUCCCCAGAAAAGUUUUCCAGAUAAAGCCCCAGUUAAUGGAACUGAACAGACUCAGAAAACAGUCACUCCAGCAUACAAUCGAUUCACACCAAAACCAUAUACAAGUUCUGCCCGACCAUUUGAACGCAAGUUUGAAAGUCCUAAAUUCAAUCACAAUCUUCUGCCAAGUGAAACUGCACAUAAACCUGACUUGUCUUCAAAAACUCCCACUUCUCCAAAAACUCUUGUGAAAUCGCACAGUUUGGCACAGCCUCCUGAGUUUGACAGUGGAGUUGAAACUUUCUCUAUCCAUGCAGAGAAGCCUAAAUAUCAAAUAAAUAAUAUCAGCACAGUGCCUAAAGCUAUUCCUGUGAGUCCUUCAGCUGUGGAAGAGGAUGAAGAUGAAGAUGGUCAUACUGUGGUGGCCACAGCCCGAGGCAUAUUUAACAGCAAUGGGGGCGUGCUGAGUUCCAUAGAAACUGGUGUUAGUAUAAUUAUCCCUCAAGGAGCCAUUCCCGAAGGAGUUGAGCAGGAAAUCUAUUUCAAGGUCUGCCGGGACAACAGCAUCCUUCCACCUUUAGAUAAAGAGAAAGGUGAAACACUGCUGAGUCCUUUGGUGAUGUGUGGUCCCCAUGGCCUCAAGUUCCUGAAGCCUGUGGAGCUGCGCUUACCACACUGUGCGUCCAUGACUCCUGACGGUUGGUCUUUUGCUCUAAAAUCAUCCGACUCCUCGUCGGGUGAUCCUAAAACCUGGCAAAACAAGUGUCUUCCCGGAGAUCCAAAUUAUCUCGUUGGAGCAAACUGUGUUUCUGUCCUUAUUGACCACUUUUAACUCUUGAAAUAUAGGAACUUAAAUAAUGUGAAACUGGAUUAAACUUAAUCUAAAUGGAACCACUCUAUCAAGUAUUAUACCUUUUUUAGAGUUGAUACUACAGUUUGUUAGUAUGAGGCAUUUGUUUGAACUGAUAAAGAUGAGUGAGCAUGCCCCUGAACCAUGGUCGGAAAACAUGCUACACACUGCAUGUUUGUGAUUGACGGGACUGUUGGUAUUGGCUAGAGGUUCAAAGAUAUUUUGCUUUGUGAUUUUUGUAAUUUUUUUAUCGUCACUGCUUAACUUCACAUAUUGAUUUCCGUUAAAAUACCAGCCAGUAAAUGGGGGUGCAUUUGAGGUCUGUUCUUUCCAAAGUACACUGUUUCAAACUUUACUAUGGCCCUGGCCUAGCAUACGUACACAUUUUAUUUUAUUAUGCAUGAAGUAAUAUGCACACAUUUUUUAAAUGCACCUGGAAUAUAUAACCAGUGUUGUGGAUUUAACAGAAAUGUACAGCAAGGAGAUUUACAACUGGGGGAGGGUGAAGUGAAGACAAUGACUUACUGUACAUGAAAACACAUUUUUCUUAGGGAAGGAUACAAAAGCAUGUGAGACUGGUUCCAUGGCCUCUUCAGAUCUCUAACUUCACCAUAUUACCACAGACAUACUAACCAGCAGAAAUGCCUUACCCUCAUGUUCUUAAUUCUUAGCUCAUUCUCCUUGUGUUACUAAGUUUUUAUGGCUUUUGUGCAUUAUCUAGAUACUGUAUCAUGACAAAGACUGAGUACGUUGUGCAUUUGGUGGUUUCAGAAAUGUGUUAUCACCCAGAAGAAAAUAGUGGUGUGAUUUGGGGAUAUUUUUUUCUUUUCUUUUCUUUUCUUUUUUUUUUUUUUUUGACAAGGGGCAGUGGUGGUUUUCUGUUCUUUCUGGCUAUGCAUUUGAAAAUUUUGAUGUUUUAAGGAUGCUUGUACAUAAUGCGUGCAUACCACUUUUGUUCUUGGUUUGUAAAUUAACUUUUAUAAACUUUACCUUUUUUAUACAUAAACAAGACCACGUUUCUAAAGGCUACCUUUGUAUUCUCUCCUGUACCUCUUGAGCCUUGAACUUUGACCUCUGCAGCAAUAAAGCAGCGUUUCUAUGACACAUGCAAGGUCAUUUUUUUUAAGAAAAAGGAUGCACAGAGUUGUUACAUUUUUAAGUGCUGCAUUUAAAAGAUACAGUUACUCAGAAUUCUCUAGUUUGAUUAAAUUCUUGCAAAGUAUCCCUACUGUAAUUUGUGAUACAAUGCUGUGCCCUAAAGUGUAUUUUUUUACUAAUAGACAAUUUAUUAUGGCACAUCAGCACGAUUUCUGUUUAGAUAAUACACCACUACAUUCUGUUAAUCAUUAGGUGUGACUGAAUUUCUUUUGCCGUUAUUAAAAAUCUCAAAUUUCUAAAUCUCCAAAAUAAAACUUUUUAAAAUAAAGUGCUGGCUUGGUCUGUUUGCCCACUGUUUUCUAGUUUCAUGCAGCUUUAUAAUCCUGUUUUAAAAUCCUGCACACAAAUCCCUAUCACCCAGCGUCACCUACCACCUCGUCGUCUGGUGUUGCAUGCAGAAUUUCUCCCCUUGGCCAGCAUGUACAGAUGGGUGGGCAGUGCUCAUCUGAAGGGCUCAGACUGAAGUGGGGCAGAAGGACCUGGAGACAGAGUGGGAGAAGGCAGCAGGCCGACUUCCCCCUGUGGGUAAACACACACCCCUGCGUGGAGAAACACCCCUGCAUGGGGACACACGUGCGUUUGUGUGUGUGCGUGUAACCAUUUGUAUAUGGUUUUAUUCCCCAGAUAAAUAGCACGGGCAUUGUUUAAUGUCACCCACAUUUGGGGGAAGAAAAUGGGUUUAGUGAGCAUAAAUAUUCCAUUGUGGACAUCCUACUUACUUAACUGCCACCCCUGUUGACAUUUGGAUUAUUGCUAUAGUGUUUCAGUAAACACCUUUGUGGACUGAAUCCAUCUAUGUGGAUUUUAUUUUUUUCAUCUUUGUUAAGGUAUAAUUUACAUAGAGUAAGUUACUGUUUUUAAAAUGUAUAGUUCAAAUUUUGACAAACACAUACUGUUUAUUUACCACGGUUAAUACAUACAACAGUUUCUUUAUCUUCUCUAAUCAUUUGUACCCCUUUAUACUCAACCCUUCUUCCAGCCCCUGGCAGGAUGAUCUCUUCUGUUUCUAUAGUUGCCUUUUUGACAGUGUCAUAUAAAUGGAAUCAUACAAUA